AAGCUAGAAGCCUGAGGAGCCGGAGAGGGUGCUGGCUGCCGCGCGGCCGAGGUGAGUAGGGUGGGAACUCGGAAAAGCGGUUGGCUAGCGGGUGAUGAAGUCGGCUGCAGGCCUGACGGCGAUGGGAUGCCCUGGAAACAGUCAGAACAGGAGCUGAAGGAGCUCGGUUCGGGAACGCAGGGAGGCCGGCGGGAUCCUGGGCCGGUUGAGUGUUUGCCCCGCGGCCGGGAGGCAGAGACUGCCUCGGCUGAGGGCGCGUGGGUCGGGGGCUCCGGAGGAGCUGAGGGAAGUCGGCUGACUUGCCCUGAAGGCUGAGACUCGCCCACCCGCCAAUCUACCCCUACACCUCCUGCCCCCUCCCCCGACCUUCGGUCCAUCUUUCGGACCCCCGGUUCCCGCGCCGGCCGCCAGGCGGCGGUCCUGGGGAGACCGCCCUUCGCGGCGGCUCCCUUGGGUGCUGCGCCCUUAACGGGCUCAGGAGCCGGACUGCGCGGGUGCACCGCCAGCCGGCCUCCGGGAGGAGCAGUGCGCUGGCUGAUCCGCCGGGAAGUUUAACCAGCUUCCUGUGGUUGCUGUGUCGCUUUUCGCCUCCUAGAACUUCCCAGUGUAUCUUCUGACCAUGACCAGGGUUUGCAGGAAACCCCAAAGCCGGCCUUUGGGCAUUAACAACAGCAGCAUUUUAUUAUGGAAAUCUUCAAACUGUGGAGAAAUUGAACGAAGGAUAUAAGGAAUUCACUGUACUCAUUACCCAGUUUCAGUAAUUAUCAAUACGUGGGCAGUCUUGCUCCCCUAAUCCGGGUUAUUUUGCGUUUUUGAGACAGGGUCUCUGUCACCCAGGCUGGAGUGCAGUGGCGGGAUCUCUACCCACUGCAGCCUCCACCUCCUGGGCCCCAGCGAUCCUCACGCCUCAGCCUCCCCACUAGCUGGGACUACAGGCAGGCGCCAUCACGCCCGGCUUUCCCCCCCCCCCCCCUUUGUAGAGAUGGGGUCUCCUUAUGUUGCUCAGGCUAUCUUUGAACUCCUUGGCUUAAGCGAUCCUCCCUCCUUGGCCUCCCAAAGUGUUGGGAUUACAGGCGGGAGUCAUCGCACCCGGCUAUCCUGGGUUAUUUUGAAGCAAAUCCCAGACAUUAUAUAAUUUCAAUUAUUUUACAUAUUUCUAUGCCUCUGUCAUGAUGAAUAAUCAUACAUAUAAUAAUUUGCUUUCUAGAGGGGUCAAGUAAAAUAAGGGACAUAUUAAAGUGUAGACAGUGCUCAUUUAGUUUGUACUACCAGAAUUUAGGUAACUGCUACAGUGCAGUUUCAUUAUCUUGUGCUCAGGUUUUCAAAAUCAGAGUUACCAGAUAAUCUAGACAGUAGUGCUCUUGCUUUUGAAUAGUAAUAAUUGUAUUGAUAAUUUCUAUUUGUCGAGUUCUUAGUAUGUAUGAAGGACUGUGAAGUUGUUUCCACCUACUCAUUUAAUUUUUGCAAUAACCCUAUGAAGUAGGUAUUAUUAUCCCCAUGUUAGAGUUAGGAGAAAGAAAUUUGGAGAGGUCACAAUUUACCUGAAGUCACACUGCUGAAAGGAUGGGGGUGGGGGUAGAAUUCAGAAUGCUACUCUUGGCCUUUGUCAUUGCAAAGUUCUUGCUCUUUUAACUGUAACAAUGUCCUAGGAGUUGUGGAAUAAAUGGAACUGCUGUGGAAAAUUAUUUCUGUUAAGCCACAAAUCAGUAAUGGAAAAAAAAAAGCCUGAAAAUUUACACAAAUACAAACAAUAGUGAGAGAGUGUGUUUUAUGGACCAUGUGCUGCUAUGUAUGCCUGAAGAAGUACUUGAAAUGCAAAUUUGGGGAGACUUUGCCAUAUAAAUGCUUGGCUGGAUUAAGCGCCUAAUUAGGAUGGUUUUUCAACAAGUUGGAGUAAGCAUGCAAUCGGUACUUUGGUCUAGGAAGCCAUAUGGUUCGUCUCGAAGUAUCGUAAGGAAAAUUGGUACUAAUUUGUCUCUGAUUCAGUGUCCAAGAGUUCAGUUUCAGAUUAACAGCCAUGCAACAGAAUGGAGUCCCAGCCACCCAGGAGAGGAUGCAGUGGCGUCUUUUGCUGAUGUUGGAUGGGUAGCCAAAGAAGAAGGAGAGUGUUCAGCAAGACUAAGGACAGAGGUCAGAUCAAGGCCACCCCUUCAGGAUGACCUUCUUUUCUUUGAGAAGGCCCCAAGCAGACAGAUUUCCUUACCAGACUUGUCUCAAGAAGAGCCUCAGCUGAAGACCCCAGCGCUGGCAAAUGAGGAAGCACUGCAGAAGAUUUGCGCUCUCGAAAAUGAACUUGCUGCUCUCAGAGCUCAGAUUGCCAAAAUUGUGACCCAGCAGGAGCAGCAAAAUCUCACUGCAGGUGACUUAGAUUCUACCACAUUUGGUACCAUACCACCACACCCUCCACCUCCCCCACCGCCCCUGCCUCCCCCUGCACUGGGGCUCCACCAAAGUACAUCUGCUGUUGAUCUGAUUAAAGAACGAAGAGAGAAAAGAGCCAAUGCUGGAAAGACUUUGGUUAAGAACAAUCCAAAGAAACCUGAAAUGCCAAAUAUGCUAGAGAUCCUUAAAGAGAUGAACAGUGUAAAACUUCGGUCAGUGAAGAGGUCAGAGCAAGAUGUGAAGCCCAAGCCAGUGGAUGCUACUGACCCUGCUGCCCUCAUAGCAGAGGCUCUGAAAAAGAAAUUUGCUUAUCGGUAUCGAAGUGAUAGCCAAGAUGAAGUUGAAAAAGGAAUUCCAAAGUCUGAAUCAGAGGCCACCUCAGAGAGAGUGUUGAAAAGACUCGUUAAAGUCAGAACCUGCUGGACAAGAAGGCCUAUGGCAAAUCCUACUGAAGAUAAAUUUAUAAGCCUUAAGAGAAUAAGGACUAUGACAAAAACAAUCCAAACCACAAUAAUUCAUGGUAGGAAAUAUUGUGGCAUCUACAUAAUAAAAUGGUUGAGGUCCUUCUUUUGUUAAUUUUGAGGCCUAUAAUUGCUCCUUAACUGGUCAGGUAUCUUAGAUAUCAGCUGGCUCACAGGAGAAUGUAUCUUCAUAAUAUAAACCCAAACGUUGCUUAUAAUAAACUGUACAUAUAAAAAAUCUUAAAAGAAAAGUUCAAUAUUGCAAUAUAGAUGUCUAAUUUCUAGGUAAAUUUAGUAAACAGAAUAUGUUCAACAUGGAGAAAAUCACACUCCAGAAAUAAGUUAAAAAUAUUUCAACAUCUAAAAAAAAAUUCAGCAGCACCCACAGAUACAGCACAUAGAAGAAAUUAAAAAAUUAUGAAUAGUUUUAAUAAAUAACACUAAUAUCAUAUGUCUUUAACCUGUUGAUAUCGAUCUCCCUCUAUAUUUUAAGCUCUCUCUCUCUUUAAAAAGACCUGACCCUGGGUAAAGGGUAGAGGAUGGAUCAAAGAACAGAUAAUCCUGGCUGGGCGCACGCAGUGGCUCACGCGGUGGCUCACGCAUGUAAUCCCAGCACUUUGGGAGGCCAGGGCGGGCGGAUCACCUGAGGUAAGAGUUCGAGACCAGCCUGGCCAACAUGGUGAAACCCCAUCUCUACUAAAAAUACAAAGGUUAGCCAGGCGUGGUGGUGGGUGCCUGUAAUCCCAGCUACUUGGGAGGCUGAGGCAGGAGAAUCGCUUGAACCUGGAAGGUGGAGGCUGCAGUGAGCCACGAUUGAGCCACUGCACUCCAGCCUGGGCAACAGAUCGAGACUCCGAGACUCCAUCUCUCAAAAAAAAAAAAAAAAAAAAAAAGAAGAAGAAGAAAGAAGGAAAUAUCCUGAAAGCAGGGAUAACGGUUAGUUAGGAGAAUACCAGAACAACCUCAGACAGUGGUGAUAAAUGACUGGUUCAAGGAGAAUAAGAGAUAACGAGGCAGAAAAGAGAUGAAUAGAAUAGGCUAUGUAAGCAUACAAAAACCCAAAGGAUUUAAUGAGACUGGAUUUAAGCAAUGAAAGAACAGAAAGAGACAACAAUUUUACAACAGGGAAAUUAACAGUGAGUUUAGGAUAAAAGUAAACAGGUGCAGAAAAUAAGUGGGUUGAGGAGCUGUAAGCAGAGAACAUUCUAGCUUUAAUGAAUUUAAUACACAUAUCCAGAAUUUUGCAAUCAGAACACCUAGAAACUAUUUUUAUUUCAGCAUGCAUGUAAAUUUUUGUAUCAUUAGGGAAAAUAGUCUUAUUUUUAAUUCUAUACAAGGUAGAGGGCACAUUAUAGUCUUUCAAAGCUUCAGUACCUCUGAAGGUUUAAACACAUCCUGCAAGGUUGCUUUAGUGUUUGUAUCUUUGCCAAGUCUGAGAUUAUAGGAAGUGAAUGGGUUUGUGGCAUAAAUCACAAAUUCCUAAUCCAAGGAACUUCACAGGGAAGAAGAGGGGUAAAAAAGGACAACUUUGCCUCCAGGUAAAUAAACUACUGAUAUCUUCAACUAGUGCAAGGGAGAAAGGAAAUACCCCACAAGGAAGAAACCUUAAGAUUCAUAACUGGAAAUAAAAGAAGGAUAAUCCUCCUGGUCAUUAAGUCCAAGGCAGCUCAACUUUACUGUGCAUAAACUCAAGCCUAGGGUUAAACUGGCCAGGUGCGGUGGUUCAUGCCUGUAAUCCCAGCACUUUGGGAGGCCAAGGCAGGCAGAUCACUUGAGGUCAGGAGUUCAAGACCAGUCUGACCAAUAUGGUGAAACCCUAUCUUUAAUAAAAAUACAAAAAAAAAUUAGCCAGGUGUGGUGGCACACACCUGUAAUCCCAGCUACUUGGGAGGCUGAGGUGGGAGAAUCACUUGAACCUGGGAGACGGAGGCUGCAGUGAGCUGAGAUCGUGCCACUGCACUCCAGCCUGGGCGACAGAUUGAGACUCUGUCUCAAAAAAAAAAAUUAAGAAAAAGUUUUGUAAGCUAACUCCUGCAGAGAACAAGUUCAGGCUAAUGUUUAGGACAAUCAGAGGAGUCAGUGGAAGAAGGGAAGGCCUGAAGAUGACUAACAGAUUUUAGUCAUAGCAGGAGCACGUGCUCAUUUCUCUGAUUAGAUCACAUUUCACAAAACACACUAGAUUACAAUUUCAAAAAGAAUUCCAAGCUGUGUGAUAAGCAGAACCUAUUAUAAGCAGCAAAGAAUAAUGCAUUUUUCUCUAUUAAAAAAAACUCCUCUAAAUUAUAUUACCAUGGUGGCUUAAAGAGACAUAUUCUUGUUUUGUAAUAACUAUAGGACCAAGUCUAUAGCAAGAGUCCAUUUUCAACUACAACUUACACAUUUGUCACCUUUUAUGAACAGCAUGAUGAGAUCGAGAGGAUAAUCUGCUGCUCUUAACACUGAGCUGCCUCCAGUGUUCUAAAUACCAUACUACAAAGCUUCCACAUCACUGGAUCAGGAUAUAAGUAUAGAUACCAAAACCUCAAGCCCGGUUCUGCUUCAUAUUAAUUUGAACCAUUUUUUUGUCAUUAAGUUUCAUUUAUUAUCCAAUUUGACCUUCUUUAUCUCUUAAAAGGAAUAUUUAACCCAUUUAUCUUUAUUACUAACAUUGAUAUGUUUGGUCUUCCUUCUCUUGUCUUUUAGAUUUAUUUUAUUUGCUCCUGGUUUCCUAGUGAUUUAGAUAGUACAUAUCCUAUUUUAAUUUCAUUAGAGAUACUUCUAACAAUCUAAUCAUUUUUAAUGUCCCUCUCCCACUAAAACGUCCCAUUAUGCCCCCUAUUUAAAACUUCUAACAGUUAUAUUUUUCGAAUUCUCUUAUUUUACUAAAUUCAGUGAAUGUUAGGGGGUAGGCUGGAGACUCCAAAUACAAUUGUACAUUUCUUUAUACAAAUAUCAAUAUUUAGACUUAACUCUUUUACUGAUUUCCUUACCCACAGCCAAUCCUUAUUUAUUGCAAUACCAAAACAUACUUUUACUUAAACUUUCCAAUGAGCAAUACGUUCACAUGAGUCAAAAUUCAAAAGGUCUACAACUAAGUUUCUUUCCCCUCCCAUCUCCUCAAGCCACCCAGUUUCUAUCCUGGAAGCAACCAAUGUUAUCAGUUUCUGCUACGUUAUUGCAGAAAAACUAUGUAUUGAAUCAUCCUUGCUUCCUUUUCUAAAACAACCCCACUAUCGCUGAAGUAUUACUCUUUCGUGCUGUUGGAAAUCCUCAUGCUAAUAAAUAUUUUUAAAAGAUUUUUUGUACUGACAUUUAUAGUGAGAAUAUUAUAAAAAGUUAUAUUUGCUUUAUAAAAUUACUCUGAAUGGUUCCCUCUUUAUAAUCAGAAAGUUUAAAGAGCUUUGAAACUAAUCAUCAAUCUUUUAAAGAUCUUAAAUAAUUUGCCUAUAAAAUUCUCUGGCCCUCAGGCUUUUAGAGAGAUAACUCUUACACAACUUUCUCUAACAUAUUGGUUCUCAGGAGUCUUUCGCACUCUUAAAAAUUAUUGACAACCCAAAUAACUUUAACUUUAUAUGGGUUAUAGCUAUCAAUAUUUACCACAGAAAUUAAGUAUUUACCAUAGAAAUUAAAUUUUUAAUAUUUAAAUAUUUAGUUAAUUUAAAAAUAUAUAAAACAAAAUUUAUUUGAAAAUAUCUAAUGGCUAAAUAUUGUUUAAAUUUAUUUAAAAAAUUUAUUACUAUAAACCCAUAACAUGUAACAUAAAUAACAUUUUUAUUAAAAAUAACUAUAUUUUCCAAAACAAAGAAAAAUUUAAUGAGAAACGUCCGGCUGUUUCUCAUAUCUGCUAAUACACUGAAUUUACUGAGACAUCACACAUCAUGCAGCCUUGGAAAACUCCACUGUAUCCUUGAGAGAGAAUAAAAGCAAAAAAGGCAAAUAACAUCUUAGUAUUACGAUGAAAAUAGUUUUAACCUCACAGACCGCACUUUAAGUACUGCUGGAUUAAUUUAUGUUUUCUACAUUCAGUUCUGAUAAACUGUAAUUUUUAAGAAAAUUUUCUGGAUCAUACAAGUGUUCAAAUAUAUUUUUGGGGUCAAGCAAAAUAGUCCAUUUCGAUUCUUAUAUUUUCUCUUUAUCUGUGGUGUUUUCCCCUCUUAGUUUUUGAGUAUGCACGUUAGCUCCAUUCAAUCUUUAAGUUAGCUAGCAACUUAUCUCUUUUAUUGCAAACAACCAGCUCUUAGUUACAGAGUUCUACUUUUAUUUUAGUUUACUAGUUCAUUGAUUGCUGUUUUUUAUCUUUAACAACUACUUUAUCUUUUCUUAGUGUAUUUUGAUAUUAUUUUUCUAAUUUCUUGAGUUGGACUACUUAGUUGACUUAUUUCAUUCUUUCUCAUUUAUGAAUAUAAGUAUUUUUUAAGGCUAUGAAUUUUCCUGCAAGCACUGCAUUAGCUGAAUUUCAUAGAUUUUCCCAUCUAGUCUUUAAUUAUCACGUUUUUAUGGUCUACCUCUUUGACCCAAGAAGUACUUAUUUCAGAAUUUGAAAAAUUUCCAGGUGGCCAGGCCUUUUUGUUUUCUAGCUUUGCUAUUAAUUUCUAGUAUCAGUGAUCCUACGUCCUCUGUCAGUUGCCUCUCUUAUUUCUUCCCUUUUCUUUGAGACGAAGUCUCGCUCUGUAGCCAAGGCUUGAGUGAAGUGGUGUGAUCUUGGCUAACUGCAACCUCCGCCUCCCAGGUUCGAGUGAUUCUCCUGCCUCAGCCUCCUGAGUGGCUGGGAUUACAGGCACGCACCACUGCACCUGGCUAAUUUUUACUAUUUUUAGUAGAGAUGGAGUUUCACCAUGUUGGCCAGGCUGGUCUUAAACUCCUGACCUCAGGUGAUCCACCUGCCUCGGCUUUCCAAAGUGCUAGAUUACGGGCGUGAGCCACCAUGCCCGGCCUCUUCCCUUUUCUUUGUAGCAAAAGUCUCUAAAAGAGUUGUUUAUACUUGCUAUAUCUAAUUCCCAUCUUUCUGUUCUCUCUUAAAUUCACUUUAAUUUCAGGCUUCCCCUACACCAUAUCCACAUUGCUAAAUCAAUGUUAUUGAUUUAGCAUUCCUCAUCUUACCUGAAUUAUCAGCAUAAUUUGGCAAAGUUAAUCAACCAAAAUUUGAUUUUUUUUAAUGCAUGGUGUGAACAGGGUCCAAGAUUCACUUGAUUUAGUGAAAUUGCUAUUUCUACCCAUUGCAUUAUUUAUCUUCUACCUACUUCAUUACCACACUUGUCACAAAUCAAAUAUCCAUAUAUGUGUGGGUUAUUUCUGGAUUCUAUAGUAUGCCUUUAUUCUAUUGUCAGUCCUUGAAUUAACAUCACCUUGACUUAAUUAUUAUUGUUUAUAAUAAGUUUGAUAUCUAUGAGAUGUAAACUCCAUAAUUUCAUUCUUCUUCCUAAUUGUCUUGGCUAUUCUUGGAGCUGGGAUUUUUUCACUGUGAUUUCACUAAACCUAUACAGAUCAAUUUAGGAAAGAAGAAAAACUGGCAUCUUUAAAUACUGAAUCCUCCAAUCCAUAAAUAACAGUAUAUAUAUUUCUAUUUAAGUUAUCUUUAAUUUUUCUAUGUAAUCACUUACAGUUUUCUAUGUAGAGUUAUACAUAUCUUUAGUUAGAUUUAUCCCUACAUAUUUGAUGUUUCUUGAUACAAAUUCAAAUUAUAUAUUAUGUUAAUUUUGUCACUGUUACUUUACAGAACUCCCACUACGUACUGACUUUGUAUCCAGGAAAACUGCUAACUUCACUUAUUAAUCCUAACAAUUUUCUAAGUACAUAACUAUGUCAUCCAUAAAAAUGAUACUUUUUCUUUUCUAGUCCUUAUACUUUUCAUUUCUUUUUCUUGCAUUACUAUACUGGCCAGAACCUCUGAAACAAUACUGAAUAGGAAAGAUGAUGAAAGAUAUUCUUGAUUUCUCAUCGCAGAAAGAAUGUUUUAAUAUUGCGCAUUAAAUAUGAUGUUUGCUAUGGGUUUUGUAGCUAAUGUUUCAGACUGUUUAAGUUUUUCUCUGUUCCUAGCUUGCUCAGAAUUAUAAGAAAGAACAAAUACUCAAUUUUAUCAAAUGCUUUUUUUUUUUUUUUUUUUUUUGAGACAGAGUUUUGUUCUUGUUGCCCAGACUGGAGUGCAAUGCAAUCCUGGCUAACCGCAACCUCUGCCUCCUGGGUUCAAGCGAUUCUCCUGCCUCGGCCUCCCAAGUAGCUGGGAUUACAGGCAUGCACCACCACGCCUGGCUAAUUUUGUAUUUUUAGUAGAGACGGGGUUUCUCUAUGUUGGUCAGGCUGGUCUCGAACUCCCGACCUCAGAUGAUCCGCCCGCCUCAGCCUCCCAAAGUGCUGGGAUUACAAGCGUGAGCCACAACUUUUCUCCUUUAUUUUAUUAAUAUAGUGAAUUACACUGAUUGAUUUUUCACUGUUAAACCAAUCUUAUAUUCCUGGAAAAAUACUAAUUAGGUCAAAAUAUAUUAAUUCUCCCUUUGUGUUAUAGAUAUAAUUUGAUAAUAUGUUAUUUAGGAUGUUUCCUCUAUAUUCAUGAGCGAUUUGGCUGUUAUUUUUUGUUCUUUCCACAACCUUGUCAUGUUGUAGUAUCAAGAUUACAUGCUAGCCUUACGUAACAAAUUGUGAAGUGUAUCCUUUUCAGAGUUUGUGGAUGAUAUUUUUAGUUUGACAGUUUAUUUUUUUCUAGCACAUCAGAGCUAUUUUUCCUUUGUCUUCUACCUUUUUAGUUUCUGUGGAAAAUGAAACCAUCUGUUUCUGGCAAUCUCAUAAUUGCUCCUUUGAAAGUAAUACUCCACUACCCCUCAUUACUUUUAAUUCUUUGUCUUUGAUUUUGGUUUUCAUAGUUAUACUCUGGUACACUUAGGUGUGAUUUUCUUUUAAUGUUACUCUGCUUGAGAUUUAUAAUACUUCCUGAAUCUGUCCCUUAAUGUCUUUUACCAACUUCUAGAGAUUUCUCAGCCAUUGCUUCUUUAAAGACUGCUCCUGCUACAUUUUUCCCUCUCCUCUCCUUCUAGGACCUUAAUUACUUUUUCAAAACAUUUUGUGCCAGAUUACAGAUGGGAGAUUAAAAAGGUUUUGACCUUGCAUCCCUUUGACAACCAGGGUUGGGAGAGGGCUGUGUCUUCCCUCCAUGACCCUGAGCAAGCUGUGUGACACAGCUCAUCAACAGAAUAUGGAAAUGCGAUGUUAUGCCAGGGUCUGGGCCCAGAUCUUCAGACACUAUGAGUCCUCACACUUCCUCUUUCUUGAAAUGCUUGCUCUGGGAGAAAGUAGCUGCCAUGUAAUUAGUCCAACUACCCUAAGACUUCCCUGAGACUGCCAUUUAUGGAGAGAGAAAAAUGUUGGCACCACACCUAAGAGUGCAGAAGCCAUCUUGGAGGUUCCAGCCCUGGAAGAUGACAUGAGAUGGACCAAGGCCCUGGACAUAAGGCUCCAGUGUCACCAUCCCAGCCAUUUUUAAGCUGUCUGAACCAUUCCAAUCAAAGACCAAGACACUGUAGAGCACAAGCAAGCCAAACUUGAUAUAUACCCUGACUGAAUUCCUGAUUCUCGGAAUCAUGAGCAUUAAAAAUAGUGGUUAUUUUAUGCCAA